AUGGAGGGGAAAAAUCUGACCAGCAUCUCAGAAUGUUUCCUCCUGGGGUUCUCUGAGCAGCUGGAGGAGCAGAAGCCCCUCUUUGGGUCCUUCCUGUUCAUGUACUUGGUCACGGUGGCAGGCAACCUCCUCAUCAUUCUAGUCAUCAUUACUGACACUCAACUCCAUACCCCCAUGUACUUCUUUCUAGCCAACCUCUCCCUUGCAGAUGCCUGCUUUGUGUCCACCACAGUCCCUAAGAUGCUGGCAAACAUACAGAUCCAGAGUCAGGCCAUCUCCUACUCAGGGUGUCUACUACAGUUGUAUUUUUUCAUGUUAUUUGUGAUGCUGGAGGCAUUCCUCUUGGCGGUCAUGGCCUAUGACUGCUACGUGGCCAUAUGCCACCCACUUCAUUACAUUCUGAUCAUGAGCCCUGGGCUCUGCAUCUUCCUCGUGUCUGCAUCCUGGAUCAUGAAUGCCCUCCACUCCCUUCUACACACACUUCUGAUGAACAGCCUGUCCUUCUGCGCAAACCAUGAGAUCCCACACUUCUUCUGUGACAUCAAUCCCCUCCUGAGUCUGUCCUGCACAGACCCCUUCACCAAUGAGCUGGUGAUCUUCAUCACUGGGGGUCUCACAGGACUCAUUUGUGUGCUUUGCCUGAUUAUCUCUUACACGAACGUUUUCUCGACCAUCCUGAAGAUCCCAUCAGCUCAGGGGAAGCGGAAAGCCUUUUCCACCUGCAGCUCUCAUCUCUCCGUGGUCUCUCUCUUCUUUGGGACUUCUUUUUGUGUUGAUUUCAGUUCUCCCUCAACCCACUCGGCCCAGAAGGACACAGUUGCAUCAGUGAUGUACACAGUGGUAACUCCAAUGUUGAAUCCCUUUAUCUACAGUUUGAGGAACCAAGAAAUAAAGUCUUCCCUGAGAAAGUUAAUCUGGGUUCGGAAAAUUCAUUCCCCUUAG